AGUGACGAUACUUUUGGCGCGCGCCGGUUGCUGUUUCUUCUCUGGCUCCGGGACCGGCGGCGGCGGCGGCGGCAGCGGCGGCGGCGUAGGGGUGAGUUCCGACUGGGCGGACCAGGUGUGGGAGCGCGAGGAGAACUGCGCACCGAGGUCUUUCUUCCGAGCAGGCCUCGGAGCGGGGCGGACCCGGGCCCGGGGGCGAGCGACACCCUCGCUUCCGCGGACAGUCUCAUCCCGCACGGAACUUUGGGUGGUGGAGGCGGCGGGUCCAAACGCUGUCUGGAGCCAACGUCUGCCAGGCUGAACCUCAAGUGUGCGGGACUGAACCCGAGGAAAUAGCCCAGUGCCCGGGUCAGGUGGCCUUGUUCGCGAGCACAUCUCGGAGCAUCUCCCCGGUCUCAAGGUGCAGCUGUCCAGUGUGCUAGUGGCUUCACGUAGUCCAAGCGGUCUUUCUAGCAGAUUCUGACAGUAAAAGCAGUGUUUGAUGAGUGGCAGGUCCUGAGUUAAGAGCCUUUAAACGGAUGAUCUUUAAUCCGCGAUCGAUACUAUCACUGUUUUAACUCAAAUGGGUGAUGAAAAGGACUCUUGGAAAGUGAAAACUUUAGAUGAAAUUCUUCAGGAAAAGAAACGAAGGAAGGAACAAGAGGAGAAAGCAGAGAUAAAACGCUUAAAAAAUUCUGAUGACCGGGAUUCCAAGCGGGAUUCCCUUGAGGAGGGGGAGCUGAGAGAUCACCGCAUGGAGAUCACAAUAAGGAACUCCCCGUAUAGAAGAGAAGACUCUAUGGAAGACAGAGGAGAAGAAGAUGAUUCUUUGGCCAUCAAACCACCCCAGCAAAUGUCUCGGAAAGAAAAAGCUCAUCACAGAAAAGAUGAAAAGAGAAAAGAGAAACGUAGGCAUCGUAGCCAUUCAGCAGAAGGGGGGAAGCAUGCUAGAGUGAAAGAAAAAGAAAGAGAGCACGAACGUCGGAAACGGCAUCGAGAAGAACAGGAUAAAGCUCGCCGGGAAUGGGAAAGACAGAAGAGAAGGGAGAUGGCAAGGGAGCAUUCCAGGAGAGAAAGGGGGAAUGAUGGCGUGUGCCUCUUCAGGGACCGCUUGGAGCAGUUAGAAAGGAAGCGGGAGCGGGAGCGCAAGAUGCGGGAGCAGCAGAAGGAGCAGCGGGAGCAGAAGGAGCGCGAGCGGCGGGCAGAGGAGCGGCGCAAGGAGCGGGAGGCCCGCAGGGAAGUGUCUGCACAUCACCGAACGAUGAGAGAGGACUACAGCGACAAAGUGAAAGCCAGCCACUGGAGUCGCAGCCCGCCUCGGCCGCCGCGGGAGCGGUUCGAGUUGGGAGACGGCCGGAAGCCAGGUGAGGCCAGGCCGGCGCCUGCGCAGAAGCCAGCACAGUUAAAAGAAGAGAAAAUGGAAGAAAGGGACCUGCUGUCCGACUUACAGGACAUCAGCGACAGCGAGAGGAAGACCAGCUCGGCCGAGUCCUCGUCAGCGGAAUCAGGCUCAGGUUCUGAGGAAGAAGAGGAGGAGGAGGAAGAGGAGGAGGAGGAAGGGAGCACCAGUGAAGAAUCAGAGGAGGAGGAGGAGGAAGAGGAAGAGGAGGAGGAGGAGACCGGCAGCAACUCUGAGGAGGCAUCAGAGCAGUCUGCCGAAGAAGUAAGUGAGGAAGAAAUGAGUGAAGAUGAAGAACGAGAAAAUGAAAACCACCUCUUGGUUGUUCCAGAGUCACGGUUCGACCGAGAUUCCGGGGAGAGUGAAGAAGCAGAGGAAGAAGUGGGUGAGGGAACGCCGCAGAGCAGCGCCCUGACAGAGGGCGACUAUGUGCCCGACUCCCCUGCCCUGUCGCCCAUCGAGCUCAAGCAGGAGCUGCCCAAGUACCUGCCGGCCCUGCAGGGCUGCCGGAGCGUCGAGGAGUUCCAGUGCCUGAACAGGAUCGAGGAGGGCACCUAUGGAGUGGUCUACAGAGCAAAAGACAAGAAAACAGAUGAAAUUGUGGCUCUAAAGCGGCUGAAGAUGGAGAAGGAGAAGGAGGGCUUCCCGAUCACGUCGCUGAGGGAGAUCAACACCAUCCUCAAGGCCCAGCAUCCCAACAUCGUCACCGUUAGAGAGAUUGUGGUGGGCAGCAACAUGGACAAGAUCUACAUCGUGAUGAACUAUGUGGAGCACGACCUCAAGAGCCUGAUGGAGACCAUGAAACAGCCCUUCCUGCCAGGGGAGGUGAAGACCCUGAUGAUCCAGCUGCUGCGUGGGGUGAAACACCUGCACGACAACUGGAUCCUGCACCGUGACCUCAAGACGUCCAACCUGCUGCUGAGCCACGCCGGCAUCCUCAAGGUGGGUGACUUCGGGCUGGCGCGGGAGUACGGAUCCCCUCUGAAGGCCUACACCCCGGUCGUGGUGACCCUGUGGUACCGCGCCCCAGAGCUGCUGCUUGGUGCCAAGGAAUACUCCACGGCCGUGGACAUGUGGUCAGUGGGUUGCAUCUUCGGGGAGCUGCUGACUCAGAAGCCUCUGUUCCCCGGGAAGUCAGAAAUCGAUCAGAUCAACAAGGUGUUCAAGGAUCUGGGGACCCCUAGUGAGAAAAUCUGGCCCGGCUACAGCGAGCUCCCAGCAGUCAAGAAGAUGACCUUCAGCGAGCACCCCUACAACAACCUCCGCAAGCGCUUCGGGGCUCUGCUCUCAGACCAGGGCUUCGACCUCAUGAACAAGUUCCUGACCUACUUCCCCGGGAGGAGGAUCAGCGCUGAGGACGGCCUCAAGCAUGAGUAUUUCCGCGAGACCCCCCUCCCCAUCGACCCCUCCAUGUUCCCCACGUGGCCCGCCAAGAGCGAGCAGCAGCGUGUGAAGCGGGGCACCAGCCCGAGGCCCCCUGAGGGAGGCCUGGGCUACAGCCAGCUGGGUGACGACGACCUGAAGGAGACGGGCUUCCACCUUACCACCACGAACCAGGGGGCCUCUGCCGCGGGCCCCGGCUUCAGCCUCAAGUUCUGAAGGUCAGAGUGGACCCCGUCAUGGGGAGAACUCAGCCGGGACCACAGGCGUGGCUACUGCGGCUGGAGCUGCGAUGAGACUCGGAACUCCUCGUCUUACUUUGUGCUCCAUGUUUUGUUUUUGUAUUUUGGUUUGUAAAUUUGUAGAAUUAAAUCAUUUUCCUUGUUGUGGAGGAAAGAGCUGUGUUUUCUCCGUGACUUGCCCAGGGCGGAGAGGGUGGACAUCUUCGGGUGCCCACGUGGGGCAGCACAAACCUCCACACACCCUCUCCCACUCUCGACACGCACGGGGCUGGCUGGGCCGUGAUUUGGAAAGGAACUGGUGGGAGCCGGGUGGAUUGUUUAAUCUUCGGAGCUGGAGACCUGUUUCUGUGUUGGGAUGAGCGAUGCCCUCUUGCCCCAACCCACUCGUCCAGACCAGCCCUGUCCACACAGGCCCCCGGCCCCCAACCCCCAGCCCCAGCUGUGCCAGCAGACUCGACAGGUUUUUAUACAAGGUUGUUGAGUUUUAAAAUGUAUUAAAAUAUUCUUCGAGGAAAG